CUCGGCCAUCGAUGCCUCGGGGCUCGUGGCGUCGGGCCUGGCGGGCUCCCCGUUGGGCGGGGGCGGCGGUCCGAGCGGCUGCGGCAGCGGAAGCGGGUCCGGGUCGCGCAGGGCGGGGGCGGCGCAGCGGGCGGAGGCGGCCGUGGGCCGCCUGGGCAGAAUGUCACGAUGGACGAGGGCGGCACGCCCCUGCUCCCCGACAGCCUGGUCUACCAGAUCUUCCUGAGCCUGGGCCCGGCCGACGUGCUGGCCGCCGGGCUGGUGUGCCGCCAAUGGCAGGCCGUGUCGCGGGACGAGUUCCUGUGGAGGGAGCAGUUCUACCGCUACUACCAGGUGGCCCGCGACGUGCCCCGACACCCAGCGGCCAUGUCCUGGUACGAGGAGUUCCAGCGGCUGUAUGACACGGUGCCCUGCGUGGAGGUGCAGACGCUGCGGGAACACACAGACCAGGUCCUGCACCUCAGCUUCUCCCAUUCCGGGUACCAGUUCGCGUCCUGCUCCAAGGACUGCACUGUGAAGGCGAUCACUACAGCCGCCCCUGCCGAACAGAUCUGGAGCAACGACCUGACCAUCUCGCUGCUGCACAGCGCGGACAUGCGGCCCUACAACUGGAGCUACACCCAGUUCUCCCAGUUCAACAAGGACGACUCGCUACUGCUGGCCUCGGGGGUGUUCCUGGGGCCGCACAACUCCUCAUCCGGCGAGAUUGCUGUCAUCAGCCUAGACUCCUUCGCGCUGCUGUCCCGCGUGCGGAACAAGCCCUAUGACGUGUUUGGCUGUUGGCUCACCGAGACCAGCCUCAUCUCGGGGAACCUGCACCGCAUCGGAGAUAUCACCUCCUGCUCGGUGCUGUGGCUCAACAAUGCCUUCCAGGAUGUGGAGUCAGAGAACGUCAACGUGGUGAAGCGGCUGUUCAAGAUCCAGAACCUCAAUGCCAGCACCGUCCGCACGGUGAUGGUGGCCGACUGCAGCCGCUUCGACAGCCCUGACCUGCUGCUGGAAGCCGGUGACCCGGCCACGUCCCCCUGCCGCAUCUUUGACCUGGGCAGCGACAACGAGGAGGUGGUGGCUGGCCCGGCCCCCGCCCACGCCAAGGAGGGCUUGCGGCACUUUCUGGACCGCGUGCUGGAGGGGCGGGCGCAGCCACAGCUGUCGGAGCGCAUGCUAGAGACCAAGGUGGCCGAGCUGCUGGCCCAGGGCCACACCAAGCCACCCGAGCGCAGUGCCACAGGCGCCAAGAGCAAGUACCUCAUCUUCACCACUGGCUGCCUCACCUACUCCCCACACCAGAUCGGCAUCAAGCAGAUCCUGCCACACCAGAUGACCACGGCAGGGCCCGUGCUGGGUGAGGGCCGGGGCUCCGAUGCCUUCUUCGACGCGCUGGACCACGUCAUAGACAUACACGGACACAUCAUCGGCAUGGGCCUGUCGCCCGACAACAGGUACCUGUACGUGAACAGCCGCGCCUGGCCCAACGGUGCGGUGGUGGCCGACCCCAUGCAGCCGCCACCAAUCGCGGAGGAGAUUGACCUGCUGGUGUUCGACCUCAAGACCAUGCGGGAGGUGAGGCGGGCUCUGCGUGCGCACCGCGCCUACACGCCCAACGACGAGUGCUUCUUCAUCUUCCUGGACGUCAGCAGGGACUUCGUGGCCAGCGGGGCGGAGGACCGGCACGGCUACAUCUGGGACCGCCACUACAACAUCUGUCUGGCCAGGCUGCGGCACGAGGAUGUGGUCAACUCAGUGGUCUUCAGUCCCCAGGAGCAGGAGCUGCUGCUCACGGCCAGCGACGACGCCACCAUCAAAGCCUGGCGCUCCCCACGCACCAUGCGCGUCCUCCAGGCACCUCGCCCACGGCCUCGCACCUUCUUCUCCUGGCUUGCCAGCCAGAGGCGCUGAGGUGUGCUGGGUGCACUGGAGCCACCGGGACCCCUUGAGGACAUCGCCAGGCUCUGUGGCUUUUUCCCGAGCGGGAGAGGUGGAGAUGCUUAUAGCAGUUACGCCUUAGGAAGGGGACAACCAGGCCCCGCCACACGCUCACACACAAACCUGCUCACGCAGCUGUGAUGCUUGGCACGGGGUGGCCAGUGCAGAUGGAGCCCAAGGCCCCCUCGGCCUCCUGGGCAACUUGGGGUACACAGGAUACUGGGGGUGCCGCUCCUCACUCAACCCCAGGCUAGGGGUACACCUGACCCAGCUGGCCUCGGCCCGGGGCACCUUCGGCUGGUCCUGUGGGGCCCUGGACGGUGGCCCAGUGGUGGCAGGGGCUGCUCCUGGCUGUGGUUGUGCGCCCGGGGCUUGGGAGCGGCCGGUCACGCUGCUGUGGGCCCGAGUGUGUUGCAUGUCCACGCACCACCCGUUCAGGGCCCUGAAUAAACAGUUGGCAACAGCA